ACCCCUCUCCGGAGCUGCGGCCCGAGUUGGCGCACUCGAUUUUCACUGCGCGGUUCCAAGAGGAGACAGCCGCCACUGUACCGGGCCUCAUAGCCACUUCCUAGAGGUAAAGAAAAAGUCAACCUCCUUGGCUGAUGAAUCACGGCAGUUUCUAAGUAGCAUUUCCUGGAACGUUCUUAAUGCUUCCCAUUUUCCCAGCAAAGUAAAAAACAACUUUUGUUUAAAUUCAGAUUUGGGUGAAAGCAGGUGAUCUUAAUUGCACACCUAUUGAAAUAAACCUGUAGUUUCUAGAAGUGGAAGAAAAUUUGCUGAGACGUCAGCUGGGGAUUCUUCCUGGAGAACUCCAGAAAUGGAGAGCUUCCACACCAGAUUUAGUGCCUGGACACCUUUUAGCAACAAGUCAUUAAAUAGACAGCUCUUUCAGGAAAGAGUGGCUCUUAUAAGUCAUUGGUUUGACCUCUGGACUAACAAGCAACGUCAAGAAUUCUUAUUCGCAAUUUUUUUAAGAUGCACUAAAUCACAAUUAAGGUUUGUCCAAGACUGGUUUUCAGAAAGGAUGCAAGUGGCCAAAGUGGACUUCUCUACAGUGUUACCACGCUUCAUUUCUCUAUAUAUCUUUUCCUUUUUGAGUCCGAAAGAUUUGUGUGCCGCUGCCCAAGUCAGCUGGCCCUGGAAGUUUUUAACUGAACAGGAUUGCUUAUGGAUGCCCAAAUGCGUUAAGUUCGGAUGGUUUCUGCCCUAUACUCCAACAGAUAAUGAGUAUGGUGCUUGGAAGCGCCAUUACAUUGCUUGUGUGUCCCACUUAGACUGGCUGACACCUAGGGAGGCUGCUGCUACUUAUGGGACGCUGAAUGAACCCAAAACAGAAGAUGAGGAACUACUGGAGAGACAAAGAGAAAAGUGCCUGAGGAAAAGAAUUUGGGAGAAAAUUGCACUACGUAAGAAGGAGUUAUUCAAAGUUCGACCCCCUUGGGUGAGUGGAACUUGCUGCUCUAGCGUGCUAAAGCCCAGAUGCCAACCACGCCUCUCCCAGACUGUAAGGGAGCGAGUGGGAUUACAUGAAGCUUUGGAGAAACAGCUUGUUUUGACAUCGUUAGAAACCUUGCCCAAGCGAAGCAAUAUUUCUGGAAGCCAUUCCUACCCUUUAUUAUCAAAGAAAAAUUGGCAUGGAGUUCAUAAAAAUGAUGACAGAUCUUCAUAUGCUCUCCGGCCACACUUCAUGUUAAUAUCAUCCCGGAUUCCUGCGUAUGAGAUGGUGAUGGAGAGUGUGAAGGCUGGUGUUGUUUCUGUGGUAUAUGAACACAGCGUAACCUUGGAAAGCCUUCUGUAUCUUAUAGAAAAAGCUCUGGAUGGGCAGAAGGCACAGAGCAUCGGAAUAUUUAGCGAUGGAGACAGCAGAGAAAUCAAUUUACUCCAAGGCUAUAAAAUUGGUGUUAAAAAUUUACUGAGGCCUGAAGUGAGAGAUUUCUGGGAGAAAUUAGGAAGCUAUGUGGCCACUGAAGAAGAAGGGGGUCACGUGGACUUCUUCGUGCCCCUUGGAGCAUCAGAGGCAGGAAUUGAAGUUCUUUCCCAGCUGUCUCAACUAACUGGCACGUUCUUUACGGCCCCCACUGGGAUUGCAACUGGCUCUUACCAGCACAUUCUUAGUGAUUGGCUGGGAUCCCAAUGGGGAAAGGCCCCCUCUUCCAUCUACUUCUGCGAAUCGAAGCUACAGACGUGGUCCAGCUUCACAGACUUCCUAGAAGAAACCUUGAAAACAGUAAGGAAGCAGCUGUAUCCUUUCUUCAAGGAACUGCAGAAGAGCAUCAGUGGCAGGAUGAUAGGGCAGUUUAUGUUUGACACCAUGGGUAUGACCAACAUUCUAAACAACCAAGAUACUGCGCAAGCUCUGGCAGAUGGAUUGAUGGAGUUGUCAAAAGAAGAUUCUGACAAACCUCUGGAAUUUUUGUCGUAUUUUCUGCUGAAGAAAUGUGGCAAAAAGAUCAAAGAUGUUGAAGGAAAUGUUAUUCCAACAAAAUGUGACCCAAAGACAACAUUCAGUUUAUUCAUGAAGGAAAGAAAUGUUGUAGAAGACAAUUCUUGGGACACAAAGUCCAGGCUCAGCAAAAAUGAUUUAAAUUUUGAAGCACUGAUUAAUCUGGAGAGAAUACUCCAGAAGGACUCAGCAGAAAAGCGAGCUAGAGUUGUCAGAGAACUCUUACAGAGUGAGAGAAAAUACGUGCAGAUACUGGAAAUUGUGAGAGAUGUUUAUGUCGCACCACUGAAAGCAGCAUUGUCAUCAAACAGAGCGAUUCUGAGUGCUGCCAAUAUCCAGAUCAUUUUCUGUGACAUUCUACAGAUUUUAAGUCUCAACAGGCAGUUUCUAGAUAACCUGAGAGACAGACUGCAGGAAUGGGGCCCAGCUCACUGUGUGGGAGAAAUAGUCACGAAGUUUGGAAGCCAGUUAAACACAUAUACCAAUUUCUUCAACAAUUACCCUGUCAUUCUGAAAACUAUUGAGAAGUGCAGAGAAAUGAUACCAGCAUUCCGAACUUUCCUGAAGAGGCAUGAUAAGACCAUUGUUACCAAAAUGCUGAGCCUGCCAGAGCUGCUGCUGUACCCAUCCCGAAGAUUUGAAGAAUACCUUAAUCUUCUCUACGCUGUCAGGCUUCAUACCCCUGCAGAGCAUGUUGACCGUGGGGACUUGACCACUGCAAUUGACCAAAUCAAAAAAUAUAAAGGUUAUAUAGAUCAGAUGAAGCAAAACAUCACUAUGAAGGAUCAUCUGUCAGAUAUACAGAGAAUCAUCUGGGGAUGCCCUACUCUAUCAGAAGUAAACAGAUAUCUGAUUAGGGUACAAGAUGUAGCCCAACUUCAUUGCUGUGAUGAAGAAAUAAGUUUCUCUUUAAGGCUCUAUGAACACAUCCAUGAUCUCAGCCUUUUCCUCUUCAAUGAUGCCCUGCUCGUUUCUAGUCGGGGCACAUCUCACACUCCAUUUGAGAGGACUUCAAAAACAACCUACCAGUUCAUUGCAUCAGUGGCCCUUCAUCGGUUACUCAUAGAAAAUAUUCCAGAUUCCAAGUAUGUCAAGAAUGCAUUUAUUCUUCAGGGUCCAAAAUAUAAAUGGAUUUGUGCUACAGAAAUAGAGGAUGAUAAGUUCCUAUGGCUGUCAGUACUUCGAAAUGCAAUCAAAAGCAGUAUGGAGAAGUGAGACCGAACUUGAAAACUUCAGGGGUGCCAAUUCUCCCCAGCAAAGACAGACAACAUGUAUUUUCUGUUCCAAAAUAUCCAGUAAGAAACAGAAUAACUGUCAUGGAUGAUGAGAUAAACUAAGAUGACCCAUAGGAUCUUUCCAACUUUUAAACUUUAUCACUUGUGCUCACUUAUGUAGAAUGUAUAAGUACAUUUUGAGUCCAAAAUUUUGAACUACUUCUUUUGGUAGCUGUAUUUCAUGGAUAAUAUUAUUUAGAGUAAUUUGAUGUGAUGAAACCUAAGACAGAGCAAGCACAUUGUGUAAAGCUUUGUUUUAUGAUCUAAUGAAAAAAGCAGAAUGAAAGUGUUUCUUAAGUGAUCAGUCUAGAAAGAUAUUUUAAUUUGUUGGUGAUUUACCAUUUUUAACAUUUUCAUGAAACAAUUAUUGAUUUAAAAUAUGGAUAAGAGGGCUGGGCAUGAUGACUCACGCCUGUAAUCCCAGCACUUUGGGAGGCUGAGGUGGCAGAUUACCUGAGGUCAGGAGUUUGAGACCAGCCUCACCAACAUGGAGAAACCCCGUCUCUACUAAAAAUACAAAAUUAGCCAGGCAUGGUGGCACACGCCUGUAGUCCCUGCUACUUGCGACGCUGAGGCAGGAGAAGAAUCACUUGUACCCGGGAGUCGGAGGUUGUAGUAAGCUGAGAUGGCUCCAUUGCACUUCAGCCUGGGUGACAAGAGCGAACCUCUGUCUCAAAAAAAAAAGAAAAAAAAAAGGACAAGAAAUACAAAUGGCAAUUUACUCAAAAACUUGUCACACUUAUCCUUAGUAUGAAUGUACUCCUCUAGAGAGCAUUAAAGAUAUACCACUACAAAGUACUAAAAAGUUUUCUAUAAUUUUUAAGUGUUAUUUAUUGGAAGGCUAAAUUCUAAGAAGCUUUAACAAAUAUUUUUGACAUUGUUAAAUUAGAAGGCUAUUUUUAAAAAGCAUAUUUUAAAAAACAAAACUAAAUGGAAACAGCAAAACUUGCUUGUAAUGAAAUACAGCUGAGUAAAAAUGUUUCUUUGAAAACAAAGACACUCAGAAAAACAGGUGUUGAGUAGUUUCCUGGGCCUUUAAUGCUUUAAAUUUAUUAUUUAACAACUAAAGCCAUACUGAAAGCCACUUGGAAACUUCAGCUGAUGUAUAUUUUUACCUAGAUAUUGUCAGGUAAAAAUUGUAUUAAUCUUGGAAGCUUGAGGUUGUCAGUUUCCCUUGUUCUUCAAAUUCUUGUUUACAGUAACAAAGUCUAUCGGUGCAGUUUAGGACUGUGAAUCUAUAGUAUUUAAACAUUUUUUCUUUCAGAAAUGAAAAUACAAAAUCUUCUAUUUCUUAAAACUUUAAAUCUUGUUAAAAAGAUGAACAAAAGUUAAAAUAUUAUGCUGUUUUAUUGGUGUAAAACCACACUUCUGAUUCUGCCAAGAU